GGGGUUGCUAGGAAGCCGCGGCGCGUCUGCUAAGCUGCAAAUGGCUGAAGUCCCGGAGGAUUAUGAUUCCGGCCCAGAUGAAGAUGGAGAGCUGGAGCCUGAGAGGCCUGAACUGCCUGGACUUCAUAAAUUGUAUGAAAAUGCCGAACCAGACACCAUGGCAAAGGCAGACUCGAAGCUACCAGCAGAGAUUUACCAAGAGCCACAGCCAGAGACCGAGGAAGAGGACUUCAAAGAGGGGGAGCCAGACAGUGCUAAGAACGUGCAGCUGAAACCUGGCGGGACGUCCCAGGAAGGAAUUGCCAAGGAGUCCAAGAGAGACGUACCAAGCGAAACUGAACCAGGGAUACACCAAGAGGUAAAGUCGGAAACAUCCAGAGAGAUGGGAGAGUUUUUCAAAGAUUUGGAGGCCCCUAUGGAUGAAACGCAUAAAGAGUCAGACCUAGAGCCACCAGAGGAGGCUAAACCAAAUGUUACAGAGGAUGUGUUCCUAGAGUCAGCUAUGGAAACAGAUCCAGAUCCAGUGCCACCAACGGAAACCAUGUCUGAGGUUUCGGGGGCCACAGUCAGAGAGAGAAAUUUAGAAUUACUAGAGGAGGAGACUGAACCGGGGGUUCCAGAGGAAUCACUUAGAGUGCAACAUGAAGAGACAGGUCUAGAGCCUCCAGAGCAGACCAAACAAGAUUUUCCAAGUGAGAAACUAGGAGAAUCACUUGAAGAGACAGAUCUUCAGCCACCAAAGAUGACCAAACCAGAGACUCCAGAGGAGACACAAAGAGAGUCAACUGAGAAGAAAAGGACAGAGCCACCCGAGCAGGCUAGACUGGAAUUUCUGGAGAAGGAACCAAGAAAGUCUAGUGAGGAGGCAGGUCUAGAGCCUCCAGAAGAGACUCAACCAGAGGUUCCAGAGGAGAUGCAAAGAAAGGCAACUGAGGAGAAAGGGACAGAACUACCUGAGCGGACUAAACCAGACUUUCCAGACCACAAGCCAAGAAAGUCUACUGAUGAGAACGUUCCUGAGCCACUAGAAGAGAUCAAAUUAGAGUUUCCUGAGGAAGAAUCAAGAAAAACAAAUGAGGAAACAAUUCUAGAACAAUCAGAAAUGAUGAAACCAGAAAGUCCAGAAGAGAUAAGAAAGUCAAAUGAGAAAAAAAAUCCACAGCCACCAGAGGAGACUGGUCCAGUGCUACCACAGGAGAUCAACCCACAAGUUGAAGAGAAAACACAAACAAAGCCAACUGAGAAAAUUCUAGAGUUACCAGAUGAAACCAAACCAAGGGAGACACAUGUAGAAUUUUCCAAGGAAGACAGGCCAGAACCAAUAAAGUCUAAGUAUUCUGUAGGAAACGAUGAGCUAGAGCACCGUGAGCCUAAAAGAGGAAAGUUGUCACUAAGUGACAAAUUUAGAAAAGAAUAUUACGCAUUAGGAUCUCUCAGAGAAAGUGAAGAAUCAAUUGGUACACAUUAUGAGUUUUUGCAACCACUCCAAAAAUUGCUUAAUGUCAGUGAAGAAUGCUCAUACUCAGAUCCCUCAGAGUCUCAGACAGAAUUAAGUGAGUUCGUUCAUGAAAAGGAAGUUGUAGAUUUGUCCCAAGAGUUGAAGGAACGGGUCUCUGAAGAUGACGAAACCCAGCCAGAAAAAGGGACUGAGUUACAAUUUGAGCAUCUUAAUUGGGAUCCAGAGGAAGUUGCAGAGUGGAUUAGCCAGCUAGGCUUCCCUCAAUACAAGGAGUGUUUUAUCACAAACUUCAUCAGUGGCCGAAAACUCAUUCACGUCAACUGCUCAAACCUCCCUCAGAUGGGGAUAACAAACUUUGAGGACAUGAAGGCAAUUUCUCGGCAUACGCAGGAGCUCCUGGAAAUUGAAGAGCCAUUAUUCAAACGCUCCAUCAGCCUUCCCUAUAGGGAUAUUAUCGGCUUAUAUUUAGAGCAAAAAGGUCAUACUGGGAUAAAAUCUGAUUCCUUGACUUUAUCUGAAUUUGUCAAAGCAGCAGGAUUACAGGAUUAUGCUCCAGAAAUAACUGCCCCUGAAGAGAAUGAGGAAUUACCUUGCACUGAACCAUAGGGGAAAUCCACUUCACAGAGCUUGAAAGAUCAAACUAAAUUACUUGAGGGAAGAGGUAUGGUCUUUUUUGGUUUUCUUUUUCUCCUUUUUUUUUUUUUUAUUUUUUUGAGACAGAGUCUUGCUCUGUCGCCCAGGCUGGAGUGCAAUGGCACAGUCUCAGCUCACUGCAACCUUGCGAUUCUCCUGUCUCAGCCUCCCGAGUAGCUGGGAUUACAGGCAUCCGCCAUCAUGCCCAGCUAAUUUUUGUAUUUUUAGUAGAUAUGAUGUUUCACCAUGUUGGCCAGGCUGGUCUGAAACUCCUAACAGUUGAUCUGCCCGCCGUGGCGUCCCAAAGUGCUGGGAUUACAAGCGUGACCUACCGCACCUGGCCCUUUUUCUCCUUUUCAUUAAGGAUCAGUUAGAACUGCUGGCUUCAUUCCUAGUUGUGUCUCUGACUUAUGGUACCCUCCCUUUCUUUUUGCAAUUUAACCCCUUGUUAAAACAAAGAUAGUCACGCUUAUCUUUCUGGGUAAUUAUAAGAAUUCCUGAGCCGGGCAAGGUGGCUCACACCUGUAAUCCUAGCUCUUUGGGUGGCUGAGGCGGGCAGAUCACCUAAGGUCAGGAUUUCAAGACCAGCCUGGCCAACAAGGUGAAGCCCUGUCUCUACUAAAAAUACAAAAAUUAGCUGGGCAUGGUGGCACAUGCCUGUAGUCCCAGCUACUCAGGAGGCUGAGGCAGAAGAAUCAUUUGAACCCAGGAAACAGAGGUUAUAGUGAGCUGAGAUGGUGCCACUGGACUCCAGCCUGGGUGACAGAGUGAGACUCUGUCUAAAACAAACAAACAAAACAAAGCAAAACAAAAUUCCUGAAAAAUUCUAGUAAUGCACCUUGUAAUAGGAACAUGUUGGGGAAAUAUAAUUAAAAAUAAAAUCUCCUGCCAA